AUCCACUCACCUCCUGAGGUGCUAAAGAACCCUGUGCUGCCUGUGACUCCGCUCCUGAACACCCACCACCGAGAUGUCCUGCCAGCAGAGCCAGCAGCAGUGCCAGCCCCCUCCCAAGUGCACUCCCAAGUGCACUCCCAAGUGCCCCGCCCCUAAAUGUCCCCCUAAGUGCCCUCCAGUCUCUUCCUGCUGCAGUGUCAGCUCCGGAGGCUGCUGUGGCUCCAGCUCUGGGGGCGGCUGUGGCUCCAACUCUGGGGGCUGCUGCAGCUCUGGGGGUGGUGGCUGCUGCCUGAGCCACCACAGGCGCCACAGGUCCCACCGUCGCAGACCCCAGAGCUCUGACUGCUGCAGCCAGCCCUCGGGGGGCUCCAGCUGCUGCGGUGGGGGCAGCAGCCAGCACUCUGGAGGCUGCUGCUGAAGUGGACCUUGACUUCCUCUUCCUUCUGAUUCUGCCUGAAUA